GUUCCUGCCGCCGAGUCCGCCACGGACGGCGCGUUUCCCGCCUGAGGCGGUUACGGAAACGCGGAGACUCGAGACUUGAAGCCAGCUUAUUCUGGACCCACGCAGGCGACUGAAGACGAUGGGACCCACUGCCCUGCAUUCGGUAAGUCCCGGGUCUAACGGAUGAUCCAUAUAUUUCAGGUGAGGAGCAAAAGAAGGGAUCCACCUAUUCAGUUCCAAAAUCUAAGGAGAAGUUGAUGGAGAAGCAUUCCCAGGAAGCCAGGCAGGCAGACAGGGAGUCGGAGAAGCCUGUGGACAGCCUCCACCCGGGGGCCGGGACAGCCAAGCACCCGCCGCCGGCAGCUUCGCUGGAAGAGAAACCUGAUGUAAAGCAAAAGUCCAGCAGGAAGAAAGUGGUCGUUCCACAGAUCAUCAUCACGCGAGCGUCGAAUGAGACGCUAGUCAGUUGCAGUUCCAGCGGGAGUGACCAGCAGAGAACCAUUCGGGAGCCGGAGGACUGGGGCCCCUACCGGCGGCACAGGAACCCCAGUACAGCAGACGCCUAUAAUUCACAUCUCAAAGAAUAAACAAGCACCUUUGCAUGGCACUCGCUACUCCCUGCGAUAGGCGUCUCGGGAACAGCCGCCUCACCCUGUGAGAAGCCGAGGCCCCUUCUCCAGUGCUCUCGGGGAGGUUGCACCAGGCCCACCCCACCCUGUGAGAAACUGCAGCCCCCUUCUCCAGUGCUUUCGGGGAGGGUGCACCAGGCCCGCCCCACCUUGUGAGAAGCCGUGGCCCCCUUCUCCAGUGCUCUCAGGGAGGGUGCACCAGGCCUGCCCCCGCCGUGAGAAACUGCAGUCCCCUUCUCCAGUGCUCUCGGGGAGGGUGCACCAGGCCCACCCCACCCUGUGAGAACCUGCAGCCCCCUUCUCCAAUGCUCUCGGGGAGGGUACACCAGGGUUGCCCCACCCUGUGAGAAGCCACCGCCCCCUUCUCCAGUGCUCUCGGGGAGGGUGCACCAGGGCUGCCCCACGCUGUAAGAAGCCGCCGCCCCCUUCUCCAGUGCUCUCCAGCCCGCCCCACCCUGUGAGAAGCCAUGGCCCCUUCUCCAGUGCUUUUGGGGAGGGUGCACCAGGGCCACCCCACCCUGUGAGAAGCCGUGGCCCCCUUCUCCAGUGCUUUCGGGGAGGGUACACCAGGCCCGCCCCACCCUGUGAGAAGCCGUGGCCCCCUUCUCCCGUGCUCUCAGGGAGGGUGCACCAGGCCUGCCCCCGCCUUGAGAAACUGCAGCCCCCUUCUCCAGUGCUCUGGGGGAGGGUGCACCAGGCCUGCCCACCCUGUGAGAAACUGCACCCCCUUCUCCAGUGCUCUCGGGGAGGGUGCACCAGGCCCGCCCCACCCUGUGAGAAGCCGCAGCCCGUUCUCCAUUGCCAUUUGGUCCUGCCUUCCCCAGAGCUGCUAGCAGCUCGGUCGAGGCAAGAGUGACUGGCUCAGAGAGCGAGCUUUGUGGUAUUGAUAAAUGAAUAAAUUAGUAUGUUCAUGUUGGAA